AAGAUGUAAAUCACACAGAUGUUGGUAGAGAAAAAGGCAUACUGGUAUUGAAACUGUAAACUGGCCUGUUUACUUCGUCUCCUAACAAAAAACACUUUGGAUUCAGGUUCUCCACAGCAGUCUUCCACUGGCCACAGUGAGGGGAGCUAGGUUUCCCCAGUCUCCAGCUAGAAAAACUCAGAACAUCUAAAGAUCUGAAAGAUGGAAAAAAGAGAACUAAAGAUAUAUUCCAAGCACACAGAACAGUAUUUGUCAUACAGCCUGAAUCCUUGUGCCAGCAGCCCACAAAGAGGCAUGCCACAGGCUUCUGUUCCAAAAUUUGACAAGAUUCCUUGGCUUAGUGAGGCCAGCCUUGUAAACAAGCCAUUAGUGCUCAGCCUUCCCAGAAGAUAUCCUCAUACCUCUGCGACUUUUCUGACUUCAUCCAAGAAGAAUAUGAAUUUGCCAAUUUUGUUUCAAGUUCCAGAUGUUUUAUCUAAGGCCAGGAGGAACCAGUGUGACUCCAUGCUGCUCAGAAACCAACAGCUGUGCUCCACAUGUCAAGAAAUGAAAAUGGUACAACCAAGAACAAUGAAAAUCCCAGAUGAUCCAAAAGCAUCCUUUGAGAAUUGUAUGAGUUAUAGAAUGAGUCUUCAUCAACCCAAAUUCCAGACUACACCUGAGCCUUUCCAUGAUGACAUCCCAACAGAAAGCAUUCACUACAGACUGCCCAUUCUGGGCCCCAGGACAGCUGUCUUCCACGGAUUACUGACAGAGGCCUACAAAACUCUAAAAGAGAGACAACGUUCUUCCUUGCCCAGAAAGGAACCAAUAGGCAAGACAACGAGGCAGUGAGCGGUAGGAGCUCAUCACCUCCCAGACUCCCAGAGAGAAAAUAACCUCGCCAAGCCAAUCUUUGACACUGGCACCUUCUCCUCACAAUUUUCUCUCUUCUCCCAAAAGAUGAUUUAAUUUUGCCUUCCUAAGAUUGCUGGUAUUCUAGCUCUUACCUCUAUGUUCUUUCUCACGUCUCCUAAAGACAAAAUUGUUUAAUUUACAUGAUUAUAAAGAUCUGUUUAUGAAAAUGGAA